UGAAAUACUUCUGGUCCUAAGCAUUUCAGAUAAGGGAUAUUCGAUCUGUAUUAGAACAUUAUGUCCUGAGUCAUUCAAGCCAGUUAAUGCCAAAUUCUGUGGAUUCUGUCUCCAUAGUAGCUCUUCUAUUUUUUCUUUCCUCCUAUCUCCCUUUGUUACCUUAAUGUAGGCUCUUCAGACUAUCAGAGUACUUUUCCUGAAGUAUGAACCACACAGAAACUUUUAGCGACCCUUGUUGCCUACUGAAUAAAGUUAAACCUUAGCUUGGCAUUUUAGGUUCUCUGUUUGAUACUAGCUGUCCUUUAUAAUCUUUUCCCUCUCAUUCCCCCUUCAUCUCUCUUUAUGCUUUAGUCAGUUUAUACUAUUCACUGCCUCCUCGAUGGUGCUCUUCUUGUUGCCACCCUCCAGAACUUGUUCAUGUUAUGCCUUCCUCCUGGAACGUUAUCCUCCGAUCCCCAAUUUCUGUAUUUUGAAAAUAUAUAUCAUUCAGAAGAGUUAUUGUGAAGAUUAAGUAAAAUAAUAUAUAUGAAGUCAAUGAAAAAUCUGUGUAAUACAUGUAUUAAUUUAUUCAGUAAGUGGUAGCUAUUAUUAUGAUUUGGCUUUCUGUCACCCCAAAUAAUCCUUAACUUUGGAUCAUCUUGUCCAGGACCCUGGCUCUUUGCAGUUUUUCUAGGGGAUUAAUCCCACUGGGACCCAUGUUGGCGCCUACCCUUGUACUUCAGGUAACCUUUGAAGCAGACCUGGACCUACUACAUCUCUUUCAGAUGGGAAUAGUUUCUCAGCACAGCUGUAUUCAGAAAGACCUUAAGAGUUGAAUAGAAAGACUCUAGGCUUUGGAGUUUGAUUUAUGCCAGAUAACCUUACCAGCUAUGUAACUGAAUUUUUUUUUCUUAAUUUAUGAAAGGGAAUAGUAAUGCUUAUCUCACAGGGUUGUCGUACCGAUCAAAUGAAACAUUUGAGAAAAUAUUUAACACUGUCUUGGAGCAUCUAACUACUUAAUAAAUCUUUAUCUUCUUUUCUGUCUUAUCCCUGUAGUGUCCUCCCCUAGGACAUGAAGAAACAUACAUGCAAACCUUCAGGUAUAAAUGCAUGCACAUAAUCCUCAAACAUCCACAUAGGCACAUAGGUACAUACUCACAUAUGUACAUACUCACAUACAUGAACAGAAGCAUAUACAUCAGAAUCUCUACCUUUGAUAGUAGCCUGAUAUUGGAAUUUUUGUCCUAGAUAAAAUUUAUAUGGUAGGAUUUGAAUUUACUGUCUGAUGACUGUUACAUGGAAUCAUUGAUCUUGUACAUAGAGAGUUGGCUGUUUUUCCAUUUCUGUUAAUCUUAACAGUUUUGAUUUGAUGGUGUUUAUCUUUCGCGCUUUAAACUAUUUACUUUUUAACAAUAUCUAAAAGCUGCUGUUUUCUAUAGUUACAUGUCUCUCCUCUUUUUUCAGGUAUUUAUGCAGAAGUUACUUUCUCAAUGAAGCCUUCCUUGAGCUACCUCAUUUCUUGUGGUGCCCAUACUUAUUAGUAUUAGGCCAUACAUUUUUACUUAUUUAUCUUAUUUGUUGUCGAUCUCUCCAUGUGUGUUAGCCUAAUAAGGACACAGACUUUUUGUCUGUUUUGCUCACUGUCAUAUCCUAGCAGCUUAGUAGGUACUCAGUAAAUAUUUGAAUGUGUGAACUUCAGCACUGGUUUAUUUUCAAAACGUCUCUGUAUUAAUACAAUAAAGAUUCUUUAAGUGCUUUUGGUAACUGUAUACAGGAGACUUUUUAAAAAAUCUUUGGAGUAGUUGACAUAAAUCAACUUAAAUGAAAUGGAAAAAAGAAGUUUACAUACAAUUUUAUGGUUUGUGAUGUGGUAUUGGAACCUCUUUUUUGCCCAUGCCAAAGUUAUAUACACACGCAUUGAUACUUAUUCAGCAGCUGUUUCAUUAUAUAUUUUAUGCUAAGGAUGGUGCUAAGAAUUGGUCCCCUUCCUCAAGAAGUUUAUAGUUCAGUGAAGAGACAACCAAACUGCUUUUGCUUGGUUGUGUCUCAUCUUUACCACCUCAAAACAUUAGAGAGCCCUGAGGCUCAGUCUUCAAAUUUCUUUUCUAUAUUUGCUCCCAUUGUGAUUUUGUAUUGUCUCUUGGUUUUGUAAAUUUUAUGUACUUACUGAUGAUUCUCAAAUUUUUUCUCUAUCUAGGACCCUUUGUCCUUGGACAGAUUGUCUGCACUUGGAUGUAUAAGGCAUCUCAGAUUUAAUAUUCAAUACAGUCUCUUGAAUUUGGUCCCCAACAAGAGGCUGUGUCUCUAGAAAUAGCAUCUCUAUUCAUCCAGCUGCUCAGACUAAGACUCUUAGAAGUCAUUCUUGACUACUCUAUUUCUCACACCCUGCAGUAAAUCCUGUUGGCUCCAUCUUCAAAAUACAUGCCCAAAUGACCCAUUCUCUCCAGACCCGUGUCUGCUCUGCCCCUCCCCUGACCUGCAAGUUUUCGCUCAUUGAGAUUACUACAGUAGCCUCCUAUCUAGUCACCUGCUUCUACCUUUCCCCUCUGCACUGAUUUUAAAACAAAAAAUCUUGCCAUUUUUAUGCUGAAAAUCCUUCAAAACCUUACCAUCUGACACACAAAAAAAGCCUAAGACUUUCCCGUGCCUGUAAGACCUUAUUUAACCUGUCUCCUCCCAUACCCUUACUCCAUCUCUUACUAUCUCCUCCCUCUCCCCACUUUGCUUAUUGCUUUGUAGCCAUACUGCCCUCCUUGCCACUCCUCCAGUGUGCCAAACUAUCCUGUCUCAGGGCCUUUGCACAUUUUAUUCUUUCUGCCUGUCCGUCUCCUUCCCCAGAUAUCUGUAUGGCUUAUACCCUCAAUGACUUCCUUCAGGUAUCUGCUUAAAUAUUUUAAUUGAAAGGCCUUCCCUGCUUCCCUAUAUAAAAUAACAUUGACCUCCUCCCUGUCUCUACCCUCUGGGCCUGCCAUUCCCUAACUCUCUUAACCUGCUUUGUUUUCUUGAAUAGCAAUAAAUAUUUAUUUCUUCCAUGACAAUAAAUACUAUAUGCUUAUUUAAGAGUUUGUGGUAUUUGUCGUCCCUGUAUAUAUUGUACAACAGUUUCGUAUGGGCAGAGACCUGUUUUUAUUCACUGUUAUAUCCCCAGCACUUAGAACAGUGCCUCGUGUGUUUAGGCACUUAGUAAAUAUUUGUUGAGUGAAAUGCAACAAGUACAAAACAAUAUGAUCACUGUAGUAGAGAUGCAAGGUACAGUAGAAACACAUGGGAAAGAGUGACAUGACUACAUAGGAAUUGAGGAAGACUUUGCAAAGAUGCCCUUAAGCAGAGCUCUUUGGAGAGAAAAACAGGUAGGGCAUUUCAUACAAAGAAAAUAGCAUUGCAGAUACACAGAGGAAUGAGAGAACAGUGUGUUCAAGGAACUAAAAUAUAGUACUGCUACAGCAUAAUUUGUGGGGGUAAAGAUGAACUAGAUGAGGUUGAACAUGUAGUAGAUAGCACCUGAUCAUGGAGGGAUGGAGGGUUUUUGUGCCAGACUAAGGAAUUUUAGAUUUUGUCCUGUCAAGUGGGCAGUGGUAGAUAGUGUGAGCCAUUGAAGACUUCUAAGCAAGGGAUGUUUUAUUUAUAUUUAUUUAUACGUGUCUCUGUGUUUGUGUGUGUGUGUGUGUGUACGUAUUAAAAAGGUAACUAGCAACAUUGUGAAGGUUGAGUAUCAAAGCUAAACACAGCAUUUUAUUUAAGAUAUGUAUGAUUUAGGAAGAUAUGAUGUAGAAAAACAAUUACUAUCACAUGUGGGCGAGAGGAUAUUUCAUUUUAUAUUUGGACAAAAUCAUGGAUGUAUAGUGGGAAGAUGUUCUUGGCAUACUUGCAGUACAUUUGUGAAAGAGAAGAAAUGCACAAUGGAGGAUUAUUCUGUUUGUCUUUGAAAAUCCACCCUUUAAGAAAGAAGACUUUAAAAAAUUAGUUAACAGUUAUGUUGUAAGUCGUAAUGUACACUAGAAAAGUGCUUAAGGAGUACCAGUUAUGAAUCAACAAGAAAAGAUGUUACAGAAUAAAAUAAAUUGUGCUUGAAUGUCAACCUCCUUUCUUCGUAGAGGAACAGUUGGUUGUCAUUGAUAUACCUCCUGAUCUUGAUUUAUUGUUGAAGGAAAUAGUGACAGUUGUACACACAAUCAAAUCUAUACUGUUUGCUGUGGGAACAAUGUAUCUGCCUUUGUAGGACAAAUGUCUGCUUUUGCAUAUUGCAGGACUCCGCAUGCACAGAAUUUUUGAAAUGAGGGAUGAACUAUAAAAACAUUUCUUCCUUUCAUUCAAAUGUCCUAUAUUGCGACCUAGUUGGACUUUCGUUUAAAAAAAAGUCUAAAUUAUGCAGAAGGGAGACGUCAAAGAAAAAGGAGAGACUGAAGAACAAGAAGGCUGAAAGUGAAGCAAAAAAUUUAUUGCCAUAUCUUGGACCCCACAAAAUGAGAGAUUGUUUCUGUACCAUAAAUUUGGACCAGGAAGAAGUUUAUCGUACCCAAGUUGUGGAAAAAUCUUUAAGCCCAUUUUUCAGUGAAGAAUUUUACUUUGAGAUUCCAAGAACUUUCCAGUAUUUGUCUUUCUAUGUUUAUGAUAAGAAUGUUUUACAAAGAGAUCUCCGUAUAGGAAAAGUAGCCAUCAAAAAAGAAGACUUGUGUAAUCACAGUGGCAAAGAAACUUGGUUUUCAUUACAGCCUGUUGACUCCAAUUCAGAGGUUCAGGGUAAAGUUCACCUUGAAUUAAAACUGAAUGAACUGAUAACGGAGAAUGGAACUGUAUGCCAGCAGCUUGUUGUACACAUCAAGGCAUGCCAUGGGUUGCCUCUCAUAAAUGGCCAAAGCUGUGACCCUUAUGCAACAGUUUCUCUAGUGGGCCCUUCUAGGAAUGACCAAAAGAAGACAAAAGUAAAGAAGAAAACAAGCAAUCCGCAGUUUAAUGAAAUCUUUUAUUUUGAGGUAACCAGAUCCAGUAGUUACACCAGAAAGUCCCAGUUCCAGGUAGAAGAGGAGGACAUUGAAAAGCUAGAAAUCAGGAUCGACUUGUGGAACAAUGGAAACCUAGUCCAAGAUGUUUUCCUAGGUGAGAUUAAGGUUCCUGUGAACGUAUUAAGAACUGAUUCCUCUCAUCAAGCCUGGUACUUGCUACAGCCAAGAGACAAUGGAAACAAGUCAUCCAAAACUGAUGACCUGGGGUCUCUUCGAUUAAAUAUAUGUUAUACAGAAGACUACGUGCUUCCUUCAGAGUACUAUGGUCCUUUGAAAACUUUGCUGCUAAAAUCACCAGAUGUUCAACCAAUAUCUGCCUCAGCUGCUUACAUUUUGAGUGAAAUAUGUCGAGAUAAAAAUGAUGCUGUUUUGCCCCUUGUACGACUGCUGCUGCACCAUGAUAAACUUGUUCCUUUUGCCACUGCUGUGGCUGAAUUAGACUUGAAGGAUACACAAGAUGCAAACACAAUUUUUAGAGGAAAUUCCCUGGCUACCCGAUGUCUGGAUGAGAUGAUGAAAAUAGUGGGAGGGCACUACCUGAAAGUAACAUUAAAACCUAUUCUUGAUGAGAUAUGUGACUCCUCAAAAUCCUGUGAAAUCGAUCCUAUUAAAUUGAAAGAGGGAGAUAAUGUAGAAAAUAAUAAGGAGAAUCUGCGCUACUAUGUAGACAAGUUAUUCAAUACAAUUGUAAAAUCAAGUAUGAGCUGCCCCACUGUAAUGUGUGAUAUCUUUUAUUCUCUAAGGCAGAUGGCUACUCAGAGAUUUCCUAAUGACCCUCAUGUUCAGUAUUCUGCAGUGAGCAGCUUUGUAUUUCUUCGUUUCUUUGCUGUAGCCGUAGUAUCACCUCAUACUUUUCAUUUGCGACCUCAUCAUCCAGAUGCACAGACAAUUAGAACAUUAACUCUCAUCUCAAAAACUAUACAAACUUUGGGAAGCUGGGGGAGUCUGUCCAAAAGCAAGUCAAGUUUCAAAGAGACAUUCAUGUGUGAAUUUUUCAAAAUGUUUCAAGAAGAAGGAUAUAUUAUAGCAGUUAAAAAGUUCUUGGAUGAAAUUUCAUCUACUGAAACUAAAGAGUCCAGUGGUACGAGUGAGCCUGUGCACCUGAAAGAAGGUGAGAUGUAUAAAAGAGCUCAAGGAAGAACUCGGAUUGGAAAAAAGAAUUUUAAGAAACGAUGGUUCUGCUUAACAAGCAGAGAGCUCACCUACCACAAACAGCCAGGUAGCAAAGAUGCAAUCUACACAAUCCCAGUAAAAAACAUUCUUGCUGUGGAAAAACUGGAAGAGAGCUCUUUCAACAAGAAAAAUAUGUUCCAAGUAAUACAUACGGAGAAACCACUCUAUGUCCAGGCAAAUAACUGUGUAGAAGCUAAUGAAUGGAUAGACGUACUCUGCAGGGUGAGCCGAUGCAAUCAAAACAGGCUCAGUUUUUAUCAUCCCUCUGUGUAUCUGAACGGAAAUUGGCUCUGCUGUCAGGAGACUGGUGAAAACACUCUCGGCUGCAAGCCAUGUACUGCAGGUGUCCCUGCAGACAUCCAAAUAGAUAUUGAUGAAGACAGAGAAACAGAAAGAAUUUAUUCCCUUUUUACCCUCAGUUUACUUAAGCUGCAGAAGAUGGAAGAGGCUUGUGGAACUAUUGCAGUCUAUCAAGGACCACAGAAAGAGCCUGAUGAUUAUUCUAACUUUGUAAUCGAGGAUUCUGUAACAACCUUUAAGACAAUUCAGCAAAUAAAAAGCAUAAUUGAGAAGCUGGAUGAACCUCAUGAAAAAUAUAGGAAGAAAAGAUCCAGUAGUGCAAAAUAUGGGAGCAAGGAAAAUCCAAUUGUUGGGAAAGCAUCUUAGAGUUUAACAGAUUGGUUCAGAAGAACUGGAAAAUAUUAUUUUUCUUGGAGCUUUUCAAUUCAUCAUGUAUUUUGUUCAUGGUAUUUAAGAAUGAGCAUCCGCUUCAAUGUCAUCUGCCUCCACAUUGUAUUUAAUAUUUAAUAAUUGAAAUUAAUUGUUUGGGAAUCCUGGUAUUGAUGUAUUACUAGAGAAUUUAAAGCCCAAGAUUCCCUUCAUACCUGUGUGACCAAAUCCAUGUUUCUGCAACUUCUUUUUAAUCGAAAGAAUCUUCCUAGAAAAGCUUUGUAACAAAGGGAGAACUCCUCCGUAGCAAGAAACCAUCUCUUCUUGUAACACUCUGUUCUGUGGACUUGUUUUCACUACCAUCAGUGCCUGCUCUAUACUGCCAACAUUGUGUUUUACUAGAAAAUUCCAAUUCAUGACAGUUCAGAGCUUUUCAUUUAGUUCAUGUAGACCCUCCCACUUUAAAAAAGAAAAAAAAUAAGAAGUGUUUUUCCUUUGGUCCAUCAGUCAUUACAGGUUCCAUUCAAGACAGUGAUAGAAACUUUAGAAAACUGCCAGAGCAUACUUGAAAGUUGGUAGAUCCUUUUGCCUAAAGAUGUAAACAAAACUCAAGACAGAAGGAAUCAGGGAAUAUGUGCUAUUGUGUGCAUCUUGUUUACAUUUGGGAUCAGUGAUGGCAAAAGAAGUAAUGAGACCACUGAAAUUGUUUUCAUUGUUUUAAAUACCAGGUACUCAUUUUCUUGAUUUGAAAGUUUAACAUGACUUCUAAGGACAUCUCUUCAAAAAGAAAGUAAACAGGGAAUGAAGGUGGUGGGAAAAUCACUUCACUUCACCCACUAUUUCAUGUUGUAAUAAGGGCCACCAUAAGGAUGCCCUCCUCAUAGUGUUCGGUUCUGAUCUUCCUCGAGAACAGUCACUUGGCGCACUUUAAUAAUCUGGACUGCUCCAGAUUUGACUUUAGAUACUCCAUGGUAUCUAGUCUUUAUGAUCAGUUGAAUGAUCAGUGUUUAAGUCUAAAAAUAAUGCUUUCCUGAAAAUGUUUAUAUUUCAUUGCUGUUUCCUUAUUGCCUGCUAGCCAAAUGGAAUUUGGGCAAGCAACUCUUUGAAGACUUUUUUACCCUAGAAAUUUACUUUUGUCCUAAAAACCCUAACUGUAAAUAAGCAGUCGAAGCAAGUUGCCACCUUGAAGUUGAGGGAUACACUUUGCUUCAUCAGUAUUAAAAACCAUGGUACUCUUAUUUUGUCUUUUUUAAUUCAAAACAUUUUCUAAAUGUGGUACUUUGAACCUUGGAGUAUUUACAUGUUUCUGUUCAAAACUGUGACUUAUUAAUGUAAGUCUGCUAGUAGUACUUUUUUUGUCUGAGCAUAAGCUAUAUUUCAAGAUAUACUUUGCCAAUUUUGUUAUUGGUGGGUAAUCAUUUUUAAAUUAUAUUGUUAUUAGGUAAUUAUUUUUAAAGACUACUGGCAUACAAUCAAAGUUGUUCCAUAAAAGAAUAUAACUGAGCAAUGUAUUUCUCUAAAUGACUUGUAAAAAUCAAUGAAUUAUGUUUAAGUCUGCAUUAUGGUAGGUUAUUACUCCCAGCUCAUUUUAAAGACAAGUUUGAAAGAGUCCUUUAAAUUUUAUAAGCUUGUAGAUUCCAUAAACUACACUGAUUUAUACAUUUGAAAGAAUUUAGCCAUUUAAUAAAUUUCUUAUUCUCAAAUUGCAUUUAGAUUAAAAUUCCUUUUAAGAGUGUCUGAAAUGUCUGCCUGCGAAGAACAUGUAAACAUUGCCAGAUACCAGUCAUUAUUCUUUAGUGGCUUUUUAGUCCUCUGCUUUUUUUUUUAAGGCAAAAGAAAUAUGCAUCUAGCAUUUCUAAUACCAAAUCCCCAAUUGUGAUUGUUUUAAAGAUCAUGGUAUGAUCACAGGGACCAAGGCUGUGUGCAUAUAUAACUCUGGAUUUGAAAGGAGGAGAGUUCAGCCAUCUAGUUCUUUUCUUCACAUGACACUUUUAAACAGCCAGUUUGACUGGAAUUAACCAACUUGGCACAGCCUAAAAAAGGAGUAAUGUGAAAUUAAAUUAUUUUUCUUUGAAAGUCUUUUGAAAUAAGAGACCAUGUAAGUAGGACCCUAAGACAACCAAGGAAUUUGCUUCCAGGGCCCUCAUUCCUCUGCUGUUACUUACAAAUGUUUUAAUUUUUACUACCUGAUAUUCUUUCUCUACCUUUUCCACAUUUGAAAAUAUACAAGGCAGCUCACUUCAUCCUAAAAACCUAAAAACUCCAGGAAGGAAAGAAAAGGAUGAUAUGGGGAAAUUUGCCAUAAAUGCCGGUUCUGGUUCUUAGUUUAGCCAUUUCCAUCAGUUGAAAUUGUGGUGUGAUCUGUUGCUUGUUUCGUUGUUGUUUUGUUUUUGUGUAGCUUUGUUUUUUAAUAUUCAUUUAAUAAGAUGAUGGGCAAUAGCAAACAUUUUUACUCCCAGGAAUAUAAUUUAUCAAAUUGAACUAUUUUAUUUGCCAAAGAAACUUGUUUUUAAUAUCACGGGUAAUGGGUAAGUGUGAAAACUAGGCUUUUUUUUAUGAAACAAAAAAAGGUGACGAAUAAUAUGGCUUUUGUUUCUGUUUCUGAAGCCUGAUUUCAUUUAUGCCAGGUUUUGAAAAACAGAUCUUUUUCUUAAGUGAAAGCACCUUUAAUUUGCUCUAACGGUACAUCCUGUAAAGACAGAAUUCUGCAUAGCCUUUUAGGUGUUUUUACAGUAUGUGAAAAAUACAAGACUCAUUCUAGAGUUAAAUUACCAAUCUUGGUUGAUAUUAUCUGCUUCCAUUUUUAUUAAUUUGGAAAUUAAUAUGUUGCUAGUAAAUAUUGGUUUUUACAGUACCCAGUUUGAAAAUGUAAGUUAUCAAAACUUAAUGUAGUGAAUUUGUGUAACCAUGUUGUAUUGUUGAGAAUGUAUUUUUAUUUAAAUUUUAUUUUCUUAUCAAGAGUAUUAUAAAAAUUAACUUUUGUAACUGUCGCUUGGAAAUAACUCAAAUAAAUUACAAGAAGCCUGUC